ACUCCGAGGCGCGGGCUGCGGGCGGCGGGCGGCGGGCGCACCAUGCCCUCCUUCGACGAGGCGCUGCAGCGGGUGGGCGAGUUCGGGCGCUUCCAGAGGCGCGUGUUUUUGCUGCUGUGCCUGACGGGCGUCACCUUCGCCUUCCUCUUCGUCGGCGUGGUCUUCCUGGGCACGCAGCCCGACCACUACUGGUGCCGCGGGCCAAGUGCCGCGGCGCUGGCCGAGCGCUGCGGCUGGAGCCCGGAGGAGGAGUGGAACCGCACGGCGCCCGCCUCCCGCGGCCCAGAGCCCCCCGAGCGCCGCGGCCGCUGCCAGCGCUACCUCCUGGAGGCGGCCAACGACAGCGCCUCCGCCACUAGCGCUCUCAGCUGCGCGGACCCACUCGCCGCCUUCCCCAACCGCUCGGCUCCCCUUGUGCCGUGCCGCGGCGGCUGGCGCUACGCCCAGGCCCACUCCACCAUCGUCAGCGAGUUUGACCUUGUCUGUGUCAAUGCGUGGAUGCUGGACCUCACCCAAGCCAUCCUGAACCUCGGCUUCCUGACUGGAGCAUUCACCUUAGGCUAUGCAGCAGACAGGUAUGGCAGGAUCGUCAUUUACUUGCUAUCCUGCCUUGGUGUUGGCGUCACUGGGGUUGUGGUGGCCUUUGCACCAAACUUCCCUGUGUUUGUGAUCUUCCGCUUCCUGCAAGGUGUAUUUGGAAAGGGGACGUGGAUGACUUGCUACGUGAUUGUGACAGAAAUAGUAGGUUCGAAACAAAGGAGGAUUGUGGGAAUCGUGAUUCAAAUGUUCUUUACCCUUGGAAUCAUAAUUCUCCCUGGAAUUGCCUACUUCAUCCCCAACUGGCAAGGAAUCCAGUUAGCCAUCACGCUGCCCAGCUUUCUCUUCCUCCUUUAUUACUGGGUGGUCCCUGAGUCUCCCCGUUGGCUGAUUACUCGGAAGAAAGGAGAUAAAGCAUUACAGAUCCUGAGACGCAUUGCUAAGUGCAAUGGGAAAUACCUCUCAUCAAAUUACUCAGAGAUUAAUUACCAUGGCCCAGAGACCAGCCAUGAGACAUAACAUGCUUCGCUGUCAACAACAUUCAGGAUUGGAAUUCCAGAGAUGGCGUGUGCUACUGGCUUAUGGCUGAUACGUAAGAGAAUCUCAUCUAUCUCUAAAUGUUCUGCCUUAAGCCGCACAAAGGACGUACCAGUGAACAAUGAGUUACCAUGUGCAGAAAAUAUUCUGCAAAUCAAGAACCAGAAAAGUAAGCAACCCGCAAACUCCAAAACUCAUUACAUGAUUGUGAUCUUUAUUUUGAGGUGCAUCUAAACUGAUCUUCAAACUCUUCAGCUAUACCUGACUUUCUCUGGAAUACUUCUCAGCAUUUUCAAACUAAACCAAAGGCUUUCUGAGUUACAUAAGGAAGGCAAAAUUUGGAUAUUUGACAAAUUUGGAAGCACUGAAAAUGGAGGAAAUUCCGAGAUGACAGUGGUUUUGGUUCUUGUGGUUCUUGUGGUUUUGGUUCUUGUUUUUUGAGGGGUGCAGAGUUGGGUUACUUAAGACUCUGUGCAUGGCUCAGGCAUCAUUGGGCUGUGCAACACUCGUCUCAUGUCCUACUUGAUUUUCUUCUCCCUUUCCUCCUCUAUUCCCACUCUUCCCUCGGCAGGUUCCCACUCUAAUGUGUCUGAUUUAUAUGUUUGCUAUUAAUGUGUUCUUAUGAAGUGGAGUGUGCUGUGUGUAUUCAGGUGAUAUAAAUGGUAUUGUGCCACUCCAGAUCUUGUAUUUCUUACUUUUUCACUCAACUAUGUGUUUUAAGUGUCUACCCAACUUGUUCAUGUGUGAGUGCAUUGCUUCCAACUGUCGUGUGAUUUUCAUUAGGCCAUACCUGCUGUGUCUCUGGUCUCCAUCUUCCUAAUGAUGGGCACCUGGGUUGCCUUCAGUAAUUGUGAUCGGUGUUUUCAUACAUGUCCUUUUCUGACCUGCGUAAGGCUCUCCAUGGAGUUCAAGGCCUAGAAGCGGAUCCCUUGGGUCCUGGUGUGCAGGCAAGCUUUGGACCCUGAAUAACGCCAGCUUGCUUUCUGUGUCUACCGCACUAGUGGGACUUGUGGGUCCCUAUUGUCUACAUCUAGAUUUAGUAUGCUUCAGUUUCCUAAUUUUUCCAGCCCCCUCAGUGCUUUAAGUUGCACAUCUCUAGUUACUGGAGAUUCUUUGUACCUUCACUGGAGCACUUGGAAAACAGAAGAAAUCAAAGGGCAGUCAGGACUCUCCCAGCAGGCAGGGACCAGGUCAGAGUCAGGAUGAAGACAAAGCACCCUGAGCAAGAAGCAAUGGAAGAGAUGCUUGUGACCCGAGCUGAUGGGGAAGGUUGAGGGCAACGCAGAGACCCCACUGCCGACUUGCCAAGAAAACGUGCAGGAAAUGAGGGAAGGCUCCAUUUUCCUGAGAAAAGGGAUGGAGGAACAUAGGCAGCAUCAAGCUCCAGCUACUGGCUCUUUGAGAAUGUAGUCGGGACUUGCCCCAGUCACCCUUGCCCUGAGAACUCAGUGACUGGGGCUAAUGUCACCCUGGCUGUCCUUGACCUGUGCAGAAAGCACUGCCAACCCUGGACAGUGGGGGAAGGGCCUUAUGUGCCCAGGCCCCAGCAGGAGACACCUACCAGGAAUCUAGUGGGACAAGGUUUCAGGGAUCCUGGAAUCCUGCCCACACCCAACAGCUGGAACAGUUCCCUCAGCUGGCGAGUGGACAGGUGGUCUGAUGAGCUCAUAUGUUAUUGAUGAUGAUGUUAAAGACCAUGUUCCCAUAGAAAUAAUUCCCAAAGCAUUCAGAAGACUGAGAAGAAGUGAUGAUAAGAAUUGUUCUGGGCAGGAGUGUGUAGUUUUGAUUUUUACUUGUGAUAAAGCAGAGGAUUUGCUUGAAUUCACUCAAACUUGCUUUUUCUCUCUCUUCAAAACAACUUUGGCUGACCAGUGUCUCAUAGACACUCAAUUUGCCUUUUCAUGGAACUCAAAAUUUUGUGUAUCCAUACAUGCUACCAUAGUUUCAGGCACUGGGCAUUUCAAAAAUGUGAUAUUUAGAACCUUUCUAUUUCCGUGAUGACUGUUGGCAUAGAUGCUGCUGGAGAUUUCGAUGACAUGUUGGAUUCAGUCCACGCAAGUUUUGAUGCAUAUUCCCUUAAUUUCUGAGCCUUUAGAGUUAGAGUUUUAGAACUGAGAGUACAUUCUCUUCUUUUUUCCUUUCUCCUCUUAUGUCAACAGGCUCCCUUCCCCACCCCCCCACCCACACACACAAACAAAAAAUAAAAAUAAAACGCUCUCAGCUUUGCUUUUAAGAAAUGAAGAAAUGUUCCAACAUGUGACCCACAGCUGCAAUCCGUUCACCUUUGCCAAUACUGAGGCUGCCCUCUGGGUCCCUCCUGGGACUGCAUAGAUAGAGGCCCAUUUGCUGUUCUGGGCAGCAUGCCCAGUCAUCUAGGAGGUGGGGGACUGGGGCACUCUUUCAGGCCAACUCAAACUAAUGGAAUAAAAUAUCUUCUCCAUGCAGUGUCUCAAAGAAAGAGCCACCUGGGCUGCAGGUGACCAGACUCGCUCAGUGCAGCACGGUAGCUCCUAGCCUCAUGUGCAGUCAAACACAUGAGAUGUGGCAAGUCUGAACUGAGAUGUGCUAUCAAGUAAACUGUACAAUGGAUUUCAAAGAUUUAAUAGGAAGCAAAGAGUAUGGAACGCCUCAUGAAUAAUUUCAUAUUGGUUACACCUUGAAAUGAUCAUGUUUUGGAUCUAUUGGAUUAAAUGAAAAGUAUUAUAAAUUAAUUUCCCCUGUUUCUCUUUAUGUUUUUUAAUGUGGCCACUAGAAAAUGUAAAUGUACUCGUGUGGCUCACAUUAUAUUCUUACUGGACAGCAUUGGUCCAGAGGACUGGGAUUUAUUUUUAACUACUUUAAUAAACAUCAAACAUUUGUGAUAAUUUUAAUACAAAUAUUUCCCCAUCGUAUAUGCUCUUGCAUGGUAAAUAUUUUAUCUACUCUUGUUUUAAAGGAUAAGGAGGUUUUCAAAAAUUGCCGAAGUACUACAGGUAAUUUGGCAAAUUCUCUUUUAUGGGUACCAGAUAGUGCUAUUUCCACCCAGAAGCUGGCUACAGCUCUGUAAUGUGACAUGCUUACUCCUGGCUAUUCUGGGCUGGUCCUCGUCUGACUAAUGAGCUCAUUAUCCACUGGGCAGUGGGAUGGAAGGACAUGAGCACCUCAGCUGUCACUGCCGAGCUUCCUCCCAGCCCCACCAGGCCCUCUGGUUCCUGAUGCUUGUCUGUAAGACCAAUGGGUACUUUAACUUUUGAAGGUGGUUUCUGGUUCCCCCAAUCGGUGAGCCCAAAGACCUCAAAUAACAUUUUAUUCACACAGACUUCUUAGAGAUGAAAAGUUUCUAGAGAGCAGAGCCUUUAGGGAACUAGUGAUGAUGCAUUCACUGAAUAAAUCACAGUAUUAUACUCAAGAGCAAAUACGUUUUCUUUCUUAUUGGUGUCAUCUUUCCUUGUGAAAUACGGCAACUGAUGAAGAAGUCUCCUAUUGAGAAUAACCAGACGAAAUCACAAGGCUAGACAAGCAGCUACUAACACCAUCCCCUUCCCCCUGCCCAUGGUAAACCCUGCUGGCAAAUGUAUUUCUCCCUCCUAAACCUGGGAGGACUCACGUUUCUGCACCCAGAGCCCCAGGUGGAAGUAAACAAUGGGAGUGAGCCGAUGAGGUGGGAUUGCUGUUCCUUGACUCUUAGUGCUUCUCAUGCUAGUCUCCUGGGGAUGCAGUUAAAAUGCAGAUUCUCUCUCUAGAUCUGGGGCGGGGCUUGUUCAGCAGGCUCCCAGGGGAGACCAACGCUGCUGACUUGUGGGUCAUACUUUGAGUUGCAAGGUUGCGUACGUGGUAUUUGCCAGUGUGCACAUUCAUGAAAAAGUAUCCUGCCUUAAGCCUGGUAGAUCCACAGUUCCAAAUCAACAUUAAAUACAUCUGGUAUACUUAAGAAAAUUCAACAUAAAAAGAAAUCCAUUUCUUAAAAAAAAAAAAGGCAGAGCAACCAUUCUCUUUAUCUGAGGACCUUUAAAAGCAUCUGCCUUUAUGUGUCACAGCAUUAGCUACUAAUUACUAAAGGAAAAAGUGCUGGGUGAAUUAUCACCUGAAAAUAAAGUAACUCUCAAAUGUUAUAAAACAUAAGAUUAAUGUUGACAGCCUCUGUUACUAUGACAUAUUGUGUGCCAGGUGUGUGUGUGUUAUAGGUGCAUAUAUGUAUAUAUAUACACACUUGUAUGUAUCUGUGUAUAUGUACACAUAUCUAUGUAUCUAUAUAGACAGAUGGGUUAUUUAAAUGAAUUUUCAAAACACUAAUAAGGUGUGAUUUGAUAAAUGAAUAAUAUUUAAUAAUAAUAUUAAAAUAAUAUAUUUGAAUAUUAUUAUUCUCCUGCUACUGAUGAGAAAACUAAGGCUCAAACAGUUUAAGUAACAUGCUAGUAAAAAAAUGUUCUGAGUAGAAUACCACAUGUCUGGCCUAACCCUGACUGUCUUUUUUCUGACCCGAGACCAGUCCUCCACGUGGGGAGCUCUGAACACCAUAUUUAUAACAGAUGGUUAUUUAUAAUGUCUUUCUCUUCUUUGGCAAUUUAAAUGAAGACGUCAACUUGAAGAAAUGUUUCACCAGGAAGAAUUGCAAAGAGAGCUGAAUUAAUCAAAGAAAGACGAAUAAAGUGUUCUUUUAAUAUGGAGUACAUAAUUGUUGAUGGAAAACACAGUCUUGGCAGAAUUAAAAGAUAAUCAAAGAGAUGAAUAGGGCAAAUAGCAAUUCAGCUCAUUAAAUAAAUACAAGGAAACUAACCUCUGCAGUUUAACCUUGAGCGAUACCUUUUCCCAUGAAUAGAGAGUGUCGAUACUAGGCAACAAGCCUCUGAACAGAUAGUGUUACCCGGAACAUCACCCUUUUCUCCCUUUGCUUCAAAUCAAAACCAGCAUCCCCCAUUUAGACAGCAUAAAAGGUAUGACAAAACGGGACGCCAAGUGAGACACUGUUGAUUCUGUUUCUAUGAAAUUCUAGAAAAAGCAAAACUGUCAUGACAGAAAGCAGAUCUGGGUUUCCAGAGCCCAGAGUGGGGGGAGGGGACUGACUUCACUGAGACACAAGGAAACUUUUGGGGAUCAUGGAAAGGGUCCGUACCACGGUUGUGGUGGUGGUUAUAAGACUAUAUAUUUGUCAAAAGUCUUCAAAGUGUGCACUUAGAAUUGCUGAAGUUUAUUGUACAUAAAUUACAUGUAAAUAUCAUAAAGUGCAUGUAAAUGGUAUGUGAGGUAAUAAAGCAAUUUUUUAAAAACAA